GCCACUGCAAUCCAGCCUGGCAACAAAGUGAGACCCUGUCCUCAAAAUAAAAAAUAAAUAAAAAUAAAACACAACACAGUGCCUCAAAAGUUGGGAACAGAAGUACGGGCAAAGACUCAAUUGAUAAAUUCAAACCAAAAAAGCAAUAGUUCAAAUAUUUGUGUAAGACAAGGUUGAAUUCAUCACAAAAUGCUCAGUUGAGUUGCAUUUUUUUUUUGAAACAGGGUUUCCCUCUGUUGCCCAGGCUGGAGUGCAGUGGCACGAUCUCGGCACACUGCAACUUCACAUCCUUCCAUCCCUGCCCUCAGAUUUCUUUCUAUGAUUUGUAAAAUGCUCUCAUACCUACAGACAUGUAGAUUGCUCUUUUUUCUUGAUGUUCGUAUAGGUUUCUUUGAACUAAUUUGUGAAAGAUACGUGUGUGUUUGGCUUGUGGGUGAGUAGAGAAAAGAUGGUGAAAAAUGAAAAAUGGCAUGGAUUUGCUUUGAAAUAUUUCCUGUCCCAAACAUCCAGGGCAGCUAAAUUUAAAUGUUUAUGUUUUAUAAUUUUCAAAUUAAAAAAUUUUAAUGGACACAAAAUAAUUGUACAUAUUUGUGGGGUAUAUAGUGAUGUUUUGAUUCAUAUAAUGUAUAGUAAUCAGCAGGGUAAUUAGAACAGCCAUCAUCUCAAGCAUCAUUUUUUUGUGUAUUGGAAACAUUCAAUAUCCUCCUUCUAGCUAUUCAAAACUGUAUAAUAAUUAUUGUUAACUAUAGCCAUCCUACAGUGCUAUAGAACACUAGGGCUUAUUCCUCCCAUCUAGCCAUAAUUUUGUAUCCUUUAACAAAUCUCUCCAUAUUCUCUUCUUUCCCCUACCUUUCCCAGUCUUUGUCUUGUAGCCUCUAGCCUCUGUUCUACUUUUUACUUCUUUUUUUUUUUUUGGAGACGGUUGCACUCUGUUGCCCGGGCUGGAGUGCAGUGGUGCGAUCUUGGCUCACUGCAACCUCCGCCUCCUGGGUUGAAGCGAUUCUCCUGCCUUAGCCUCCCAAGUAGCUGGGAUUACAGGCCCCCACCACCAUGCCCGGCUACUUUUGUAUUUUUAGUAGAGACAGGAUUUCACCAUGUUGGCCAGGCUGGUCUCGAAUUCCUAAGCUCAAAUGUUCCACCUGCCUUGGCCUCCCAAAGUGCUGGGAUUAUAGGCAUGAACCACUGCGCCCAGCCUACUUUUAGCUUCUAUGAGAUCAACUUUUUUAUGUGACUACAUGAGUGAAAACAUGUAUGUUUAAUUUUCCAUACCUUAUUUAUUUCACUUAAGAUAAUGUCUUCUAGUUCUAUCCAUAUUGCUGUGAAUAAGAGAAUUUCUUUUUCUUUUUUUUUUUUUUGUGAUGGAGUCUUGCUCUGUCACCCAGGCUGGAGUGCAGUAGUGCGAUCUCGGCUCACUGCAACCACUGCCUCCUGGCUUCAAGUGAUUCUCCUGCCUCAGCCUCCCGAGUAGCUGGGAUUACAGGUGUGUGCCACCACACUGAACUAAUUUUUGUAUUUUUUGUAGAGAAGGGUUUUGCCAUGUUGGCCGUGUUGGUCUUGAACUCCUGACCUCAGGUAAUCUGCCUACCUUGGCCUCCCAAAGUGCUAGGAUUACAGGUGUGAGCCACCACGCCUGGUGCCCAAGAAUUUCAUUCUUUUUAAUGGCUGAAUAGUAUUCCAUUGUGUAUAUAUACCACAUUUUCUUUAUCCAUUCAUCUGUUGUGGGACACCUAGUUUGAUUCCAUAUCUUGGGUAUCAUCAAUAGUGCUUUGAUAAACAUGGGAGUGCAGAUAUCUCUUUGAUGUAUUAUUUCCUUUUCUUUGGAAAAAUGCCUAGUAGUGGGUAGUUCUAUUUGUAGCUCUUUGAGGAACCUUCAUACUGUUAUUUUAUUUGUUUAUUUUUUUUUUGAGACAUCGUCUCGCUCCAUCACAGGCUGGAGUGCAGUGUUGCGAUCUCAGCUCACUGCAGCCUUGACCUCCUGGGUUCAGGCGAUCCUCCUGCCUCAGCCUUGAGUAGCUGAGACUACAGGCGCAUGCCAACAAGCCCAGCUAAUUUUUGUAUUUUUAGGAGAAACAGGAUUUUGCCAUGUUGACCAGGCUGGUCCUGAACUCCUGACCUCAAGUGAUCCACCUGCCCUGGCCUCCCAAAGUGCUGGGAUUACAGGCGUGAGCCACUGCGCCCGGCCCAUGCUGUUCUUUAUAGUGGCUAUACUGGUUCACAUUCCCAAACAGCGUACAAGAGUUCCCUUUUUGCUGCUUCCUCACCAGCAUUUGUUAUUUUUUGUCUGUUUGAUAAUAGCCAUCCUAAGUGGGGUAAGAGGAUACCUUACCCCAAUUUUGAUUUGUAUUUCCCUGACGAUUAGUGAUGUUCAGCAUUUUUUCCAAAUAUUUGUUAGCCAUUUGUAUGCCUUCUUUUGAGAAAUGUCUGUUCAAAUCAUUUGCCCAUUUAAAAAUUGAAUUGGUUGUAUUUUUUUCUUUUGAGAUGUUUGUUUCUUAUAUAUAUACUGGAUGUUAAUCCCUUGUUGGUUCAAUAGUUUGCAAAUAUUUUCUCCCAUUCCGUAGGUUGUCUUUUUGUGCUGUUGGUUGUUCCUUUGCUGUGCAGAAGCUUUUUAGUUUAAUAUAAUCCCAUUUGUUUAUUUUUACCUUAUUGUCUGUACUUUUCAGAUCUUUUUUUCUCUCUUUCUUUUCUUUUUUUGAGACAGAGUCUCACUCUGUUGCCCAGACUGGAGUGCAGUGGCGUGAUCUCGGCUCACUGCAACCUCUGCCCCCAGGUUCAAGUGAUUCUCCUGCCUCAGCCUCCCCAGUAGCUGGGAUUACAGGCAUGCAUGACCAUGCCUAGCUGAUUUUUGUAUUUUUUAGUAGAGACAGGGUUUCACCUUGUUAGUCAGGCUGGUCUCGAGCUCCUGACCUCAUGAUCCGCCUGCCUCGGCCUCCCAAAGUGCUGGGAUUACAGGCAUGAGCCACCGUGCCCACCCUGUACUUUUCAGAUCUUAACUCAUAAACCCUUUCCCCACAUCAGUGUCCCCUGUGUUUUCUUCUAAUAGUUUUAUAGUUUCAAGUCUUACAAUUAGGUCUUUGAUCCAUUUUAAGUUGAUUUUCGUAUGGGGUGAAAGGUGGGGGUCUAGUUUCAUUCUUCUGCAUGUGGAUAUCCAGUUUCUUAGCACCUAAAUUUAAAUUUCUAGUCCAACUUUUUUUUCUUACAUUCUCAUAAGGUGAAAAGAGAAAGCUCUUAUUUUUUACAUUAAUGUGUGAUUAAUUUACUUAGUAAUGAAUGUGAUUUUUUUUCCCUCCAGAAGAGAAAAUAUGAUUUUUAUUAACUAAGUUAAUAUUUUGAGUUUUUUUUUUUCCUACUACAGUAAGUGAAGUAUGUCUUGAGAAGACUACAAAUUCUCUACUUUCAUUACUGGCAGGUGGAAUGUAGUCUUGUAUUACAAGAAUGAACACUUGUGAAUAGUAAUUUGUUUCUCUAGUAUUUACCAUAUACUAGGGAUGAUACUUAGUAUGUUGGAUGCUUUGUAUCAUUUGAUCAUUCCAGUAUCCUGAUAACAUAGCUACUAUUAUUAUCCCUGUUUUACAGAUGAGAAAACUGACAUUCAAAUAGGUUAAAUGAUUUGUUCAAGGUAACACAGCAAGUGGCAGAUUUUGGACUUGAACAACCGUGUCUUCUGACACCUCCAGCAUUUAUGUAUCUUGUCAUUUACUGGUAAAACAGAGAGUAUUUCUGGACUUUUUCAGUAGCUGAUAUCUGAGCUGUUCCAUCAGCCAUCUUGAUGGCUGGAAGUGUGGAAGAGGAUGGGUGAGACUCCAUCAGCUCACUAAGAUCCUGACUUGGCAAAAUAGAUUCAGUUUCAUGAUAGACUAGAUGGUGUUGUAAUAUAUAAAUCCUACCACUGGGCCUUUUGCGUGUAGAUUGGUAGUGAGUAUUGUGUAAUUCCCUCCUUCCAUUUUCUCACUGACUCUGAAAAGACUCAUAAGCCACGAUUAUUUUACUAUUUAGUGUGACUGGAAGCACCAUGUGGUGCAGAACUUUGAAAUGAAUGAUAUAAGUGUGGUCAGCUGACUAGUCUUUGGGCCUGAGAAGUUUAUUGUGAUUGGAUGGGAUAGGUGUGGGGAAAUAUUAUAAGGGAAAGAACAUUUUUUAAUGACAGAAAUUUAAAUACAAAAUUUAUUUUGUAUUUCAUAGAAAAAUUUAUAAAUUGCCAAAUAUUUUACCAUCAUAUCAAAAGAAGUAGAAUUUCUGAGAGAAGUUUUAGGUCUACCAUUUAUUCUGCUGGCAUUGUAAAGGGAUGUGGGUUCUGAAAAUGAGUAUAGCAUGCAAACAUCAGUAAUGAAAAAGAGACCUGCUACCUGUGACAUUCAUUUGGUGGAAGAGUUUUGCUGCUUUGAGGUAUUUAUAGAACUUAACCAGAGCAAAUGUUAUUUAGUUCAAUUUGGGGGGAUAAGGUAACUUACUUUUUUUUUGUUUUGUUUUUGAGACAGAUCUUCACUCUCACCCAGGCUGGAGUCCAGAGGUGUGAUCUCGGCUCACUGCAACCUCUGUCUUCCGGGUUCAAGUGAUUCUCCUGCCUCAGCCUCCCAAGUGGCUGGGAUUACAGACAAUCUGCUUCAUCCUGAUUCUGCGGCAUUCCAAACUGUGGUAUCCUUGGGGGUUCUCUUAACAUUGCUAUGGUGCAGAAGAUUUAAAAUCAGCCCCAAACUGUGCAAGCAGAGGCGACUCAACGGCUACGCCUUCUGUAUCAGACACGUUCUGGAGGACAAGACUGCCCCCUUCAAGCAAUGUGAAUAUGUGGCCAAGUAUAACAGCCAACGCUGCACCAACCCCAUCCCCAAAUCAGAGGAUCGUAGGUACUGCAACAGCCACUUGCAGGUACUUGGCUUUAUCCCGAAAAAAGAGAGGAAGAAAAAGAAUGAUCCUAUAGAUGAGGUGAAGGUCAGGCACCAGAUGGAUACCAUGGCCUUUAGCCUGACAGUGCCCACGUUGGCCUUGAAGAUGCCCAACGGACUGGAUGGAAUGUCCCUCUCUCCACCUGGGGCAAGGGUCCCUCUCCACUACCUGGAAACCGAAUUGGAAGACCCAUUUGCUUUCAAUGAGGAAGAUGAUGACCUAAAGAAAGGGGCAACUGUGAGAAAGAAGUUGCAGAGCAAGUUGGCCCAGAAUCGGCAGCGCCAGAGAGAGACAGAGAUUUUAAAAGUUCGACAAGAGCACUUUAGUCCCCCUCCUGCACCUUCACAGCAGCAGCCUCCGCAGCAGCACUCCCACCUGUCACCUUUAUCUACUUCUUUAAAACCUCCAGCGCCACCGCAGGGUUCAGUCUGCAAGUCACCUCAACCUCAGAACACCAGCCUACCAAUGCAGGGAGUGGCACCCACCACACACACUAUAGCACAAGCACGGCAGUUGUCUCACAAGAGGCCUCUGCCCCUCCUGCCAUCCAGUAGGGCUCCCACUGUGGACCCACCCAGGACUGACCGGAUCCUCAUGAAAGCCACAGCCUUCUCUCCACACUUCUCAUGUAUAAGCCGACUGCAGAGACUGGUGAAACUGUGCACCCAGAAACAUCAGUUGGACACUGAUCUGUUUCCCCAUUUAGGUUUGGACUGGUCUGAAGAGAGCGGAGAGGAACCAGAGGACUCAGAGCAGGCCUCGCCCUACCAGGUUGCAUGGUCCAUCCGGGAAACCCUCAGAUAUCAAAGACAUGCGUCAGAUGAUGAUGAUGCGGAGAGUAGGAGCUCCAGGGUGACUCAACUUUGCACUUACUUUCAGCAGAAAUAUAAGCACCUCUGCCGCCUGGAGCGGGCAGAAUCUCGUCAAAAGAAAUGCCGGCAUACGUUUAGGAAAGCUUUGCUGCAGGCGGCCAGUAAAGAACCAGAAUGCACUGGUCAGUUAAUACAAGAACUGCGGAGAGCUGCAUGCAGUCGAACCAGCAUAAGCCGGACCAAGCUGAGGGAGGUGGAACCAGCAGCAUGCAGUGGAACCGUGAAGGGUGAACAGUGCGCUAACAAAGCCCUUCCAUUCACCAGACAUUGUUUCCAACAUAUCCUCUUGAACCACUCUCAGCAGCUCUUCUCAAGUUGCACAGCCAAGUUUGCAGAUGGACAGCAGUGCUCUGUGCCAGUUUUUGACAUUACACAUCAGACACCUCUGUGUGAAGAACAUGCCAAAAAAAUGGAUAAUUUCUUGAGAGGAGAUAACUCCCGUAAAGUUCAGCACCAGCAGCAGAGGAAACCCAGGAAAAAAACCAAGCCUCCUGCACUAACCAAAAAACACAAGAAGAAGAGAAGGCGUGGACCUCGUCGACCCCAAAAACCCAUUCCACCUGCAGUCCCCCAAGGGAACCUCAGCAUGCCCGCCAGCGUCUCACUGCCAGUGGAGGCCUCUCACAUCCGGAGCCCAUCCACGCCAGAGCUGAGUGCUGAUGAGUUGCCGGAUGACAUUGCCAAUGAGAUCACUGACAUUCCACAUGACUUGGAAUUGAACCAGGAGGACUUUUCAGAUGUCCUGCCACGGCUACCUGAUGACUUACAAGAUUUUGAUUUUUUUGAAGGGAAGAAUGGAGACCUCCUCCCAACUACCGAAGAGGCUGAGGAGCUUGAACGGGCCUUGCAGGCUGUAACUUCUCUCGAGUGCCUGAGUACCAUUGGGGUCCUUGCCCAGUCAGAUGGUGUGCCAGUCCAGGAGUUGUCAGAUAGAGGAAUAGGGGUGUUCUCCACAGGUACUGGAGCUUCAGGAAUACAAUCCUUGAGCCGAGAGGUGAACACAGACCUAGGGGAGCUAUUGAAUGGGCGUAUAGUACAUGAUAAUUUUUCUAGUCUAGAGCUGGAUGAGAACCUGCUCCGUUCUGCUACCUUGUCAAACCCACCUACACCCCUGGCAGGGCAGAUCCAGGGGCAGUUCUCUGCCCCAGCCAACGUUGGCCUUACUUCUGCCACUCUGAUCAGCCAGAGUGCACUUGGGGAGAGAGCCUUCCCAGGACAGUUUCAUGGACUUCAUGACGGCAGCCAUGCCUCCCAGAGGCCACAUCCUGCCCAGCUGCUGAGCAAGGCAGAUGACCUAAUCACCUCACGACAGCAAUACAGCAGUGAUCACUCACACUCCUCACCCCAUGGAAGCCAUUAUGAUAGUGAGCAUGUGCCGUCUCCCUACAGUGACCAUAUCACCUCUCCCCACACAACAUCGUACUCUGGUGAUAAUAUGGCAGCUACCUUUUCAGCAGAGAUGCCCAUCAUGGCGCAGCACUUGCUCCCAACCCAACUUGAGGUGCCACUUGGAGGCGUGGUAAACCCCAGAACUCACUGGGGCAAUCUCCCUGUCAACCUUGGAGACCCCUCUCCAUUUAGCAACCUUCUCGGCGCAGAUGGACAUCUUCUUUCCACUUCCCUAUCCACGCCACCCACCACUUCGAACUCAGAGACCACACAGCCUGCCUUCGCCACCGUGACCCCCAGCAGCUCCAGUGUGCUUCCGGGGUUACCACAGACCAGCUUCAGUGGCAUGGGGCCUUCUGCUGAACUAAUGGCCUCCACCUCUCCCAAGCAGCAACUCCCUCAGUUCAGCGCAGCCUUUGGCCACCAGCUGAGUUCUCACAGUGGCAUUCCUAAGGACCUGCAGCCCAGCCACAGCUCUAUAGCCCCUCCUACAGGCUUCACAGUAACAGGUGCCACAGCUACAAGUACCAAUAAUGCAUCUUCUCCCUUUCCCUCCCCUAACUGAGGGUGUCUGUGUGUUUGCAGGCAGGUGGGGAACCCAGUGUUUUCUAUCUUUGUUUCCUCUUUAGCACCCCUCUCCCCUUUUCCUAAAGAAGAUAUAACAGAUGGGGAUCAGAGGGGCACCCCCCUUCCCAGUUCAAUGAGUGGCCCUGCAGUGGACCUCGCUACAGUGUUCACAUGUGCUCCUUAGCACUGGUGCUCAUUCCCUCCUGGCAGGCCCACUCCGCCCCAGUGGUUUCCUUAGUGGUUCAGCACAGUGACUGGAUAGGAUUGAUUUUUAGCAGCAAGUCCUAGAAGUGGAAGAUACCUCAGAAUACCAGUGCCCUUUACUAUUUCCUAGUAUUCAGAUCAGUGCUUUCCAUUCUGUUGCCAGGUUUUUACAUAGGUGGUUCUAGAUAGAAUGAUCUUAUUAAUUGAGUUCCUGUAUAAGAGACAGCAAAUGGUGUGUGGCAGGUCAAGAUUCUGACCUAGCACCAACUGCUAAACACCACAGUGAGGCCAGGAUUCCAUUCGUAAUUGUGAUCAUGUUUAACUAAAAGAAAAAAAUGUGUCUUUUGACUGCCUGUGAGUAUGCGUGUGCCCACGCGUGUGUUUUUGUGCAGUGCAGGAAGCAGCUGUCCCAUUAGUUUGAUUUUUUUUUGUUCUCCCCUUCCCCCUACUUAAUGAGUAUAAAACUCUUACUUUUCUCCUGUCCUACAUCUCACAGUCCUAAUAAGGUUGGUCCUUCUUUUCCUCAAGUUUCCUGAAUAGGGAGGGUGGUGGACUGGUCGUGUGAGUAGCACAACCUUUUUCUGCUAAAAGUUAGCCCAAGAAGAAACAGAACAUAGAAAGCUUGGAUUCCCGUCAGUGAGGUAGGGAUGUCCUAAAAAGCUUGCCUGGGAUGACUGCAGGCUGCCGGGGUUCUGGGGCCUGAUGGUCACUUUGUCUUUUCAGACAUUUGUUUGUUUCUAAAUCCCUCUCUCAUGGAAUACAUUUGCAAGAUGUAAUUAAAGAAAAUAUUUUGAUGUGAAAAAGCAGGAUAGGUCAGAUAGAUUUGAAAAGAUGGGAUCUGUCAACUCCUUGAUCCAUCUUUUGCUUUUGAAUUUUUCAUGUUUACAGUAGUGAUUCUUUGGUAAGAUUUGUAAAAUGUUAAGACACUUGUAGAAUCAGUGUACCAGUUGUGAAGUGAUGUGUAAUAUCUGAAGGAUACACAUUUUAAAGUUUCUUUCAAAGCAGAAUAUGGAAAUUAGAUAUAAAUUUUAUUCGCCCUUUGGUCCUUUUAAAAUAAUUCAAGUACUUGGGUUUAAGUAAAUUUGAAAAUAGCUUUGGGAAAUGUUUUUAAAAUGCCAGGAUUUUAGGGGUUAAAGAUCAUAUGGGGUAGUUUAGGAAGUUUGUGACUAUGAGAUGAAUUUGUGAGGUUUCUUGCCUACCUUUUUUCCCCCCCAGAGAAGGGUGGAACUAGAUUUUAAAGGCAUCUCUACUCUGCUUUUGCUGAGUAGUUUCACUGUCCCUUGAGAUACCAUUGGCUAUUUAUACCUGAGUCUAGUCUAAUUCACAUAUAUAUAUAUUUUAAAAGUUGAGAGAACAUACCUAUUGAUGUGGUUCAAUAAUUCAUUUGUCAGGGAAUAUUUGAUCUUAAUUCCUUUCUAAUAGGUAGUGAUUGGAUGUAUUUUCCUACUUCCUGUAUGUAAUCUCUUUAUGCCAUGCUAGUUCUAACCAGUCCCUUCUUUUGAAAGCUUUUCUUUCUCUGCUUUUUAAAGGAAUGAUGGUGAUCAGCAGGCAUUAUGCAGAUACCACGUGCCUGAGGUUAUGGAGGGGAAAUGUCACAUGACUGUAUGAAAUCAUUAUAUGCCCUAUUUUGUAUUUAUUGAUGUUUCUUUUUGUGGGCCAAAAAUAUGUUUGUAAUAUAUUUAGUUUUUUUAAAAUCAUGGUAAUUGAUUGGAAGAUUUAUUUUUAAUAGCUUUGCCUUUUUUGCAGAGUGCAAAAUUUCUAAAUUAUAACUUAUGUCAUAAAGCAAAAUUAUAUUUGGUAUCACCAUAAAUUUCUAUUCUGAAUGGUGAGAACAGAUAAUUUGAAUAUUUCUCACCUGUGAGUCUAUAUUAGUAAGCUUUUUUAUUUUAAUGUACUGUAAUGAAGUGGUCACGAGUAGUUACCUCGGCUCAAAAAUGUCAUUUAGUUUGUUAAACUAUUUUCACAACCAUCAUAAGCAUAACUAGAUAACUGUCCAUUCCCAGCAGUUCAGUUUAGUCUCCAUUGUGUAUUUAAAGGUUGUCGCAGAGCAGCACAUUGACUUCCUCAUCAGCCCUUUGACAAGGAAGGGAAAGUCGUGGGUAGUCGAUUUGAACUUUUUCUGUCUACUUGUCCCCUCAUGUUAGCUGCUUGAAAUUCUUCAGUUAUGAUACAAAGCUGAGUUUGCAGUAAGUUGCACAUUUUAUUGUUUGCAAUUUUCUGUUUUAUGUGCAUUUAAAAGCCCUUCUCUGCUUUCUAGUAAGGAGGCAUGAAAUUAUCAGGAAUGUUGCUAGUUACAGCUUCACACCAAAAACUUUGAGUAAAUACAUUUUCGUUUGGAUGCCCAUGAUGAAAGCUGAGGAAAGUGGUUGAGGAAUUAUCAACAACAAACUUUUCCUCUUAUUUUAUCUAGUUCAAAACAGAUAUCAAAGUUUGCAAUUUGCUUUGCUCUUGCUGUUUCUUAUGAGUCCCUUUUUGGAAGAGAGGAGAACAUCUAUAAGCCCAGAGAGAUCUGUGUUUUUCUUUUACUUAAUAGAGCCAUUCUCGUCUAUUAGUAGGAACUUUGCUAUUAAUAUGUAUAGAAAGGAAUGAAGUGGCUUUUACUCCAGAAAUAUGAAAAUUAGUAUCUUUUAAAAUAGCACUUAUGCUAUCACAAGGCAAUACUGGAAUGAAAAACAAAUCUUAUAUAAGGUCCUAAAUAGGUAGAAACUAGCUUUUAUUCUAGUGUUGAACCCAGGAGAAAUAGUGGCAAAGAAGUUUCACUCUGUUUCUGCAGUUCUUUGGGACUAUUUAUAAAGGCCAGUUAGAUUGUGUUACUGUGAUUUAAUUUACAAAGUUGCUGCAGUUAAUGGAUACAUUCUGUGCUCUGAGAAUCUGAAUUCCAUUCUAAUGUGUGAUAUUCACUGGCUAUGAUCAGUAGUAUCUGAAGAAAAGAUGGGCUUUUUCUCCUUUACUCUCUCUACAUAAUUAUUAAUAUUAUUUUAAUUAAAGUACUUAAGACAUUGUUUUUUCUUCUGUAAAAAUGGCUUAGCAAUUUGCACAUCUGGGUAGGUUAUGUAGCUAGUAAACAACUCAAUAGUAAGUAGCAAUUAUACUUAACCCACCAAGUGACAGACUAUGCAAUGGAAAAAUUUUCUAAUUAUCGUCACAUAGCUUAGACAGCAAAGGAUUAUUUUCUCUGGUGACCUACCAUGUGUGAUAUAACUGCUUUAUAAAUGACUUCCUGAGCAAUUUCAUGUUGGCAGGCAGUGUGGUGUGUCUAGUGCCCCUCUAUGAGAAGACUAUAAUUUAAUCAGAAACAAAUAGUAGGCAUGGGGAGCAAGUUGGAAAGUGAGGUUAUUAUUUUUUUUCCUUAAAAUUGGUGUUACUGUCUUUAGUGGCUUGAGGCUAAAGAAAGCUGAUACUUUAUCUUUGCCAAAUAAUUAUUUAUAAGAUUUAUUUUUAAAUAAGCCCAAUCUCUCACCUGCAGUUAAGAAUCAUCAUUUUCUGUGACUGACACUAAAGCUCUUCCUUAUCAGAGCUUGUUCUCAAUCUGUGAUCACAGUCCACAGUGGCAAAGACAACUCUUUGAUUAGGAAGGAAACCAUGUUUGGGAUGCACAGAGGUGCCCUGUCCAUACGGUUUUCUUCUUACAUGAAAGAAUUGACCUUUCUGUUGACCUAUACCAUUCUGUUUUUAUAAAGUGGGAUUAGAAUUUGAGCAUAUCUAGUAAAUGCCGUGUGGUCAGUCCGCUGAUGCUUGCCCGCCGUCUUUGCCGUGCCUUGGCAUCCUAGGGGUGCUGGUGAUGGUCAGUGGGCAUCAUCGGUCAGCAGUGCACGUGUAAGGCAAUCUCCUCUCCUCCAGGUUAGUUCAGAAGGUCGCUAUGGGUUGGUAUUGCAAAAAGAUGAGUAUAUGAACACUAAACUUAUUAAGAGGUUUGAAAUUCAUUAAAAAUUAGUUUUCAGUUUCUUCAUCUUUCUUUUCAGACUUCUUUAAAAAUACUGUUCUUAAUCUGGUAUAUAUAGAAAUCUAAUAUUAUGGUCUUCUAAAUGGUCAACAGAACUCUCCAGUUUAAUGAGGCAAUUUAGAGGAUUCCUUGAAAGAAAAUUUCAUCAUACUGAACAGUCCUCAUUUGUAUCUCUUUUGUUACCAGUAUUUACAUUGUUCCAAGGAUUUUUUUCCUGACAAAAAAUAUAUUUCUCGGGAGUGGAGAGUUUUUUAUAUAUAUAUAUGAAAGAACAUAGAUGUUUCCCCCCGCCCAAUACAUUAACUGAAUCUUCACUGGCAUUCUGUAGAAAAGUUAAAACAGUUUAAUAAUGUCUUAACAUCUUUAUACAUUUUCCUAUAUUCUGGAGGAAACCAGAAUCAUGUUUAGUAGAUUAAAGUAACAUUUUAAAUACUACCUUUCCAAUAAUUUGUAAUAAAAUACCAGUGAAGGACAUGUUUGGAUAUCUGUUAAGCAUUUUUCCCUGACUAAUGAAUUAGGAAAGAAAACAUAAAACAUAAAUGAAUAGUUAUGUCUCUUCUAAUAAACAGUGUCAUUAAUGCUGCAGUUGUGGGUCAAACUUAGGGAGCCUUAUUUCUAAAUAGCAAAAAUUCUGUUUUCACUUCAGCCCUUAUUUUUUUUUGUUAGUUUUUCUCUGCACUGUGAUACAGAGCUAAUAAGAGGAAAUGUGACGUUUCAGAGAGAGAGCAAGCAAAUUGGGUAUGACUUUUUUACCCUAUGUUCCCCAAUACUGGGGAUGUUUGGCUACUUUGAACAGCAGUUUUUAGUGAUCUAAAGUUUAGAUCAAUACUCGUAUAAGAGAAAAAUCUAACUCUCAGUGAGCUCCAUAGGGCAGCACAGCUUUCCAUCUUCUCUUUCGCCUUCUUGCGUCUGCCCACCACAGUCCCGAAGAAUGCACACGCACAUAUGAUCUGUACCCAUCCCGCCCGAAGAGUCAUAGAAUCCUCUUCUUUCACUUGUUUCUUUUUUCUUCGUUUGUUUGUUUUUGUUUGUUUGUUUUUUAAGCUGGGGACCACUGAAGUAAGCUCUGUAUGCACCCAAAGUUCCCCUUGGAAAAAUUUUCAACACGCAGUGCAGAAGGCUCCAGUGCAGCUAAAUGCCACACCAUUGGUUCUACCUGGGGGAAUAGACUGAUUUGCCCUAAAAUGACUCCAACCUGCAUCAUUAAGGUACAGUUGGCUCCAGUGGAUUAGUGCUGAAAUGAUGGGAAGUCUGACACUUGUUGACAUUGUCUUCAUCUGUUUGGAAGGGUUGAAUCUGUUCCUCUCAACAGUGAUAGUUCUUUUCACUGUAUAGUAUUGAGUAUGUCUCAGGGAUUCCUUGUGGAAAUUAGGGCAGUUUUUAAAAUAAGAAAAUAGUUUUAAAAGAAACUAAAGGUGACUCAUCAUUGAAGAGAGCGGAAGAAAGAGGAAACAUUUGGUUUUGUAGCCCACAGUGUCUUGCAUAGGACUUUUUCCUUUCUCCUCCAGGCUCUCAUCUCAGCUUCAGAAUACAGAAUCCUUUCCCAUCACGCACAGCUUUAAAACUUUUAUUUAAAAAUUUCCUUCCCCAAUGAGCUUUCAGAAUACUUAUUGUAGAUUUUAAGAGAAAAGGUAUAUUAAUUUAUGCUAUUAACAUCACCUCAUAAAUUAUAAGUUUUAUACUAAAGCUGUAUCGAGUGUAAUGAAUUAUGUUGCCUAUGUGUUUAAUAGCUAAAUAUAUAUGAGCUUUUUUUUUUUUUUUUUUUUUUGACAAAACAAACUAGUGAAGCACCUUUUUACACUGGAUCUCUGCCGUGUCAAGGUGUAUAGCUAUCCUUUGCUACCUUGCAGAUAUAUAAAAUAAAAGGAUAUCCUGGGGCCUCAAAAUGUAGAACACCUUUAGACCAUUUAUAACUGUUCCUAGAACUGUUGAGAAUCAUGUUCUUUAGUAAAUGAUCUGUGGUUUACACUUAAGAUGGCUAGAAGCUUAGUUACAGGGUACAUAGAAAUACAUAGAUCAAGUAAAACUCCAACUACUGUAGCUGGAAUUUGUAAACUAAGUUUGUAAGACCUCUUUUAUUUCCUAUGGAGUUAUUCUUUAAUUUACAGUUUAUUCUGUAAGUUGGGAAGUAAAAUAGAGAAAAUAAUAAAUCUAGAUGUUCUCAGUGUCUUAUUCAGGAACUUUUUAUCCCUCCUCACUAAGGAAUUCCCACUGUGACUUUAAAAUAGAACUAAAUUACUUGUGUGCAUGUAUAUGUCUGUAUUUUUUACACACAUGCAAAAAUAUACAUUGGGGGCACGUGUGUGAGAGAUAUGAAUGUGUGCUUAUAUAAAAAUAGAUAAAGGUAACCGAAUGUAUUGUAGAAACAUGAUUUAUUUAGUUGAGGGUAUUGGAGUUACUUUCUCAUUGUCUCUGUUGUAUAAAUACACCAAAUUAAUCAUUAUGUUAUCUUAUGUUAAAAGGCUAGCUCUGAUAUCAUGUGCAUUUUAUGUUAACCUUUGGAUUAACUUAUAUUAUGCUAUGUUCAUAAAAUGACAUGAGAAACAGGAGGUUCUAAGAUCAGCCUCUCACUUUCGAGCAUAAAAAUAAGAGAGGGAGACAGACAGCCCCAGACAUGAGCUGUGUUUAUCUAUUGUGGUGAUGGGACCACAGAUCUAUUGAAUCUUUUUUAUGUUAAUUAUAGAUUUCUUUAUAUUCGAGUAAGAAAAUAUUGUUGAUCAUCUUUUCUUGGUGAAGUUAAGAAAAAGUAUAGGCCUUUCAUAAACAAUUUUUGGAAGGGGCUGCUUUGUUUAAGGAGUUGGUGGGAUCAUUUCACCGUGCAUAUUUCAAAGCUGGGGUGAUUUCAUUUAUUUCCAAAAUUUUUCAAAAAACUUUUACUCAGUUCUGCUGUUAUUUAUUAACUUAAGAGUGCUCCCAUCCCCAUAUUUCAGCUAUAGGAAAAUUGUGCUACCCCUGAUUCAUAUGGAAUUAAAAAAAAAUACAUCCCUUUAUUUUGAGUUUUAAGUUGUUAUUUUGCUAUACAUUUAUUACUGGAGUAUCUGGUGGUCUGAAAUAGUCAAAAGUAGAGUUGGUAUUAAAUGUUCCAAUGACAUUUAUUUUUAAUACUUAAAAAAUCAUGUACUUUGAAAUAUGUCAAAGCAACUUCUGAUAAUAUACCUGAAUUUGUAGUUGUCUCUUGAGCAUCAUUUACUUCAUCUUAGAUAUAGUGAAGAUCUAGGAAAGCUCUAUAUGCUGUUCUUUUCUACAGUUGUAUUUUUGCAGCAUCUCCUGGUUUCAUUCACUCUUGUUUUGGGAUUUUUUUUUAGAUCUGCAUAUUUCUUGUACAUAUGCAUGCAAAUGAAAGAAGGGAGUUUGUACUGGUGCCAUUUCUCCCUUCAGUUGCUGGUUAAUGGGAUUUGCUAGAAAAAAUUCUCCCGGUUGAAGGGUGAAAACAGACCCUUAUGUGUAUAUCUGUACAGAGAUGUGUAUAUGGGAUGUGGUGGCACUUUGCUGAAUGUGAACUUGCCUUGUCAAUGGAAAGAUUGAAAAGUAUUAUGUUUAUUUAUACAUUUGUAUAAAUCUAUAUAUACACGUAUGUAUAUGUGUGUGUAUAGAUAAAGCUAUAUACAUAUAUUUCCCUUAAAAAUGUGUGUGUAUAAUAGGUAAACAGCCUUUGUUAAGCAAGAUUAAUGUCUAUGGAAAGUUCUGGAUUAUUCUGUAAGCCAGAGGAGGUGACAGUCUAGAGUACAUCAUCAGAACAUACUAAAAUGGAAGUCCUUUGGAUUAUAGUUUUGUUUAUGGAUAUUACACAAUGAAUGCUUGUCUGAACAGUUCUUACUUGCCAGUUCCACUAUUCUUCAUCUUCACCACCUUCUACUGGUCAGUCUUUCAUCACUUAAAAAAAAAAAAAAAAUCACACAUCAUUGUGGUUUUUUUCCCCCUUAAUUCUGUCUCUUCUAGCCAGAAGCAUCUGGCUUAAGCAUAUUUCAUCAACUUCUCUGUUAUUUCUUUUAAAGAUCUUUAUCUCUGAAAUUUUCCCAGAAGAUACAAGUUUUGGUAAUAUUAUCAAUAGGAAUUUUGAGACUUGGGCAUUCAUCUUUGUCUCAAAAACAAACAGAAAGCCAACCUUCAAAUAAAACAAAUUUGAAAGUUUUAGCUCAAUAAUUUGGGGACAUUUUACUUAAAUUACAAAAGAACAUAAUUAUGAUUUUAUGAUCGAUAUUAGUGUUAGGUUUAUUUCCACACUUACUGUCAUUAAUUUGUCAUUUACAUAUUUUUAUUUGCUUUGUAGUUUAAUCAUAACUUCACCAUUUACAUUUUAAUGGAAAGCAUACAAGGUCACAUGUUAGCCUCUUGAAUUCUGUAACUAACUCAUUUUUCUCAUGAUGAAACUGCUUUGAUGAAUUCCUGUGUGAUGAAUUCUGCUAUAUUUCCUUUUGACUUUUCUCAGUUUGUGACAUUCUGUAUUAACUUUGCUGCAGCUCUCUAGAAAACUUGCAUCCCUAUAUAUUGUGCCUUUAAAGCUCUUAUGCACACACAGACAAAAGUGUAUAUAUACAUGUCAGAGCAUGUGUACAUAUGCUUUCGUAUGUACUCACACAGUAUGUCUCUAGUAUAUAUUGUGGGAGUAGAUAUAUAGAUAUUCAAAGGCAAUGAAAUAUUGCUCUCCAGAUAUAUAUGUAUAUAAAUAGUGUUGAUAUAACUGUAUAUACACAUGUAUAUGUAUGAGUUUUAAAUGGCAAUCUUUUACAUUUAGCAAAAUGCUGCCCCUACUGGAAUAUUGUCACUGCAGUGGCAGUUGUAUGUAAUGAUUUAAAAUACAUUAUCAAAAGUUAUUUAAAGAACAUUUAAAGUCUCAUCUAAAGACAUCCACACACUAUUUAUUUAUCUUCCUUUUCCUUUUAUUGUUGUGUUUUUCUUAACUGAAAGGGAGACUGUCAUUUUAAAAAUGCCAUCUGUCCCAUGAGAGUAAGAAAGAGCUGGAGAUUCACUUGAGGAGCUUUGUGCAUUUUUCCUCUCUCUGAAGUGGAGAUGUUCCACAGACCAGACUGUUUAUUUCACUUAUAAAGCAAUCCUAAUAUUUCCGUUAGUGUAUGUCAGCCACCAUCUCCUAGAUCAACUUAAUUCACCAAUUUGCCUCCUCCUUUCAUUAAUAAAUAAUGAUUAUUGAGAUCAUUUUGCCUGGGGGAAGUUAACUACUCCCAUGCUGCAGGGAAAUAUAUCACCUAAUUGUUAUUUUGCCUUGUUCAAAAUUCAAAUUUGAAAGAAGGCAGCUCUCUCAUGAAGCUGUCUUAAGCACAUUUUAGUUAAGGGCCCUCCCAAACUCUUUUUUCUUUCUUUCUUUCUUUCUUUUUUUUUUUUUUUUGCGAGUUCCAAGUUGCAUGUGCUUGAAAUAGAUUUAAUUCUUAUUCCCCACAGUUUAGGUAUUUUUCAUUAGUACAUCAAUUUGACACACUGAAUGCAAGACUAUUAAGGAAGAACGAUUAAAUAUUAUUUUAUUUUGUGAAGAGUUGGCAGCAGAUUACAUCUCAAGAACUUGCAGAGAGAGGAAGGUAGAUGGACAAUCCUAAAUUGUAAGAUGUUACAAAAAACAGUGAAGUAAGAGUACUCCUGAAGACUAAAAUAGAGAGGCUGGGGUUUGAGCCAUUUUACUGAGUAGCUUAGCUGGAACCUGAUAUCAGAAGUAGCCUUUAACAAAAAGCCUCUUGGCAAUUGUAUGGUACUAACAACUAGAGUACUGAAGUGUAAGUUGAAACCAAGUUGCAGUGGGAAAUCAAAGGUGAGGUAGCUUAUUUGAAACCAGCAAAUGAGACAGGUUGGACAGUUUUAAAAUCUCUUCUAACAAAGAAACUGCACGGUAGCAAGGACUAGCGGUUCUCAAAGCCCUUCUUUUUCAGUGUUCUCAUUCACCUUGGCACCCAAGUAUGUUUAACAGGCCAUGCAUUAAAAAUAAAUACAAAAAUAUAAAAGCCGCUUAAAGGGAACUUACAAACUGACAAUCUCUCCUCUGUAUUUGUGUUCAUAGUGGCUGGGAGUUUAAUUAUAUGCACAAAAGUUAGGAGCCACUUGUUUCUGCACAGACUGUAGGAGCAAGAUGAGGAGAUGGGCAGGUUUUGGUAAGAGCCCCCAGUUCUGGUGGACAGGCAUACUUGUGGCAUUGGGUGCGGCAUUGCUGGGAGGACCACGUCUUGGGAGGCGAUUGACUUUUGGUUUGUAAUUUCCCUUUAAACAAGAAGAGAUGGCUCACAUUUUCCAUAUAUAUCUCAAUGAAUGUACUGUAUUACUGUUUUAAAAAUUUGAUGAAAUAAUAAUGAAUUGGUCUCCUUUUGUUAUCUGGUCCUUGUUUAAUUUGUUUAAGGGUUUUUGUAUACAAAAGUUUACAUUUUUAUGUAUAUUUUUCUUGUGUAAAAACUGAUGUAAUAUGUGUAUGAAACACUGUAUGUAUUAUCUGUAUAUAGUGUGACAAAAUCAUUUUUCUUUCUUUCUUUUGGAUGUAUUAAUAAAUCUUGCUGUGAAGUA